GCCUUGGCAACGACCCAGCCGCGCCGCGAGGAGAGCCGGGAAUGGAGGUCGUGGCGUGAGGGGCGCCGAGCGAGGGGAGGCGCGGGCCACGGGAGUUCCGGGAGUUCCGGCGUUGCCCGGCAGUCCGCAGUCCUCGGCGGGAAGGCUGUCCCGGCGCCUCAGGCAGCUCUGCGUGGGCCGGGGUGACUUCCUCGCGAUCCCCUGCGCGAGGUGAAGGGCAGGGACCUUUGCCGCGCCUUCCACGCGCCGUGCCCCACCGGCGAGUGGCUCCAUCUUCCUCAGACUUAUCGCUCGCGGACAGGCGCCGUGGGUCUCCCGGGCCUCCGUACCGUCCUCCUUCCCAGCGGCUCCGGGAAGCGGUUCCCUGUCUUCGGACGCAUUUCACCCGCGCGGGGAGAGCUUCCCGGGAAGGUUCCACGGCGGCCGAGGGUUUCCGCGCCCGGGACGCGUUUCGGCUGAGGCCGUGGGUCCAGUCCACGGGUUCUGCCCGCACGGUCCAAUGGCCGGGGAGGCGGAGGCUCAGUUGGACCCAUCAUUGCAGGGCUUGGUGAUGUUUGAGGAUGUGACGGUAUAUUUCUCCAGGGAGGAGUGGGGGCUCCUUAAUGUGACCCAGAAGGGCCUAUACCGGGAUGUGAUGCUGGAGAACUUUGCACUCGUUAGCUCACUGGGACUUGCACCUUCGAGAUCCCCUGUGUUUACCCAGCUGGAGGAUGAUGAACAGUCGUGGGUGCCCAGCUGGGUGGAUGUGACUCCAGUCAGCAGAGCAGAAGCCAGGAGAGGUUUUGGUCUUGGCCCCGCAUGUUCCUGCCUCUCUGGCCUGCGUCUCCUCAUUGCCCUUCUCUGUAUCUGUGCAGAGCUGUCUACUGUUGGCGACUCAGUGCGUGUCUUGAAAUGUGCACAUAUCCUUAAACAGAUGGUUUGUGUAGAGUGGAGGAUGAGAGAGCCCAUCCUGAGCAUCUAAAGAGCUACAGAGUCAUCCAGCACCAGGACACUCAUAGUGAGGGGAAACCAAGAAGGCACACUGAGCAUGGGGCAGCUUUCCCACCUGGUUCCAGUUGUGGGCAACAGCAAGAAGUCCAUGUGGCAGAGAAGCUGUUCAAAUGCAGUGACUGUGGGAAGGUGUUCUUAAAGGCCUUUGCCCUCCUUGACCAUCUGAUAACGCAUUCUGAAGAGAGACCCUUCAGAUGCCCAACAGGCAGAAGUGCUUUCAAGAAGUCAGCUCAUAUUAACCCCCGAAAAAUUCACACUGGAGAAACAGCCCAUGUGUGUAAUGAAUGUGGGAAGGCCUUCAGUUACCCGUCUAAGCUGAGGAAACACCAGAAGGUUCACACAGGCAUAAAACCUUUUAAGUGUAGUGACUGUGGUAAAACCUUCAACCGCAAAGACGCACUUGUUCUACACCAGAGGAUUCACACUGGAGAAAGGCCUUACGAGUGCAGCAAAUGUGGUAAAACCUUCAGUGUUCUGUCUACCCUCAUUCGGCACCGGAAAGUGCACAUUGGAGAAAGGCCCUAUGAGUGUACAGAAUGUGGGAAGUUCUUUAAAUACAAUAAUAGCUUCAUUCUUCACCAGAGAGUUCACACUGGAGAAAGGCCUUUUGAAUGCAAGCAAUGUGGGAAAGGCUACGUGACCCGUUCAGGCCUCUAUCAGCACUGGAAAGUCCACACUGGGGAACGGCCCUAUGAAUGUAGCCUGUGUGGGAAAACCUUCACUACCAGAUCCUACCGCAAUCGGCACCAGCAGUUCCACACUGAAGAGAGGUCUUAUGAAUGUACAGAGUGUGGGAAGGCCUUCAAACAUAGUUCCACCCUCCUUCAGCACAAGAAAGUCCAUACUCCAGAAAGGCGUCAGGAGGACAGGGCACAUGGGAAGGUCGUUAGCUGCUAGCACCGUGUUCAUCAGGAAAGGUCUUAUUCCAGAAAGGAGGUUAAGGAGAGUGGCCGUGAGAGUGCCAUCCGAAAGAAGCUAAACCUUGCACAUCCCAACACCCACCCCAGGGAGAGUUCCCGUGUGUGCCUGGUGUGUGGGACGCUUUCGGGAGCCACAUUGCACUCUGACUUGCCUGGGGCUGUUGGCAGUGUCACAUCACUGAGUUUAUCCACCGCCAUCCACCUCUAUCCACCCCAUAAGGUCCCUACAGCAAGUGGGACAGCAGACCUUGUGCUCCUUGCUCUAAACAGUAGAGAAUCGUUAAUAGUGGAGCCCAAAACAGGCCUCAUUCCCUACCCUUGACUGGUUUAGCUGUGGACAUGACCCACCUCUGGCCGGAGGAGCUGAGCUGGUAUCUGCUGGGGGCUUCCUGGGAAGGUUUACCAUUUUCAUGGAAAUGGUUGACAUUACACAUGGUAUUUGUCAUGCCCUAGCAUGGACUGUCUCAUACUGCUCUGGACUAUGUGGUAAUAAAGGCUUUAUUGUUUAAGCCGCUUAAAA